AGAGCUCAGGGUGCUGAGCGUGUGACCAGCAGUGAGCAGAGGCCGGCCAUGGCCAGCCUGGGGCUGCUGCUCCUGCUCUUACUGACAGCACUGCCACCGCUGUGGUCCUCCUCACUGCCUGGGCUGGACACUGCUGAAAGUAAAGCCACCAUUGCAGACCUGAUCCUGUCUGCGCUGGAGAGAGCCACCGUCUUCCUAGAACAGAGGCUGCCUGAAAUCAACCUGGAUGGCAUGGUGGGGGUCCGAGUGCUGGAAGAGCAGCUAAAAAGUGUCCGGGAGAAGUGGGCCCAGGAGCCCCUGCUGCAGCCGCUGAGCCUGCGCGUGGGGAUGCUGGGGGAGAAGCUGGAGGCUGCCAUCCAGAGAUCCCUCCACUACCUCAAGCUGAGUGAUCCCAAGUACCUAAGAGAGUUCCAGCUGACCCUCCAGCCCGGGUUUUGGAAGCUCCCACAUGCCUGGAUCCACACUGAUGCCUCCUUGGUGUACCCCACGUUCGGGCCCCAGGACUCAUUCUCAGAGGAGAGAAGUGACGUGUGCCUGGUGCAGCUGCUGGGAACCGGGACGGACAGCAGCGAGCCCUGCGGCCUCUCAGACCUCUGCAGGAGCCUCAUGACCAAGCCCGGCUGCUCAGGCUACUGCCUGUCCCACCAACUGCUCUUCUUCCUCUGGGCCAGAAUGAGGGGGUGCACACAGGGACCACUCCAACAGAGCCAGGACUAUAUCAACCUCUUCUGCGCCAACAUGAUGGACUUGAACCGCAGAGCUGAGGCCAUCGGAUACGCCUACCCUACCCGGGACAUCUUCAUGGAAAACAUCAUGUUCUGUGGAAUGGGCGGCUUCUCCGACUUCUACAAGCUCCGGUGGCUGGAGGCCAUUCUCAGCUGGCAGAAACAGCAGGAAGGAUGCUUCGGGGAGCCUGAUGCUGAAGAUGAAGAAUUAUCUAAAGCUAUUCAAUAUCAGCAGCAUUUUUCGAGGAGAGUGAAGAGGCGAGAAAAACAAUUUCCAGAUUCUCGCUCUGUUGCUCAGGCUGGAGUACAGUGGCGCAAUCUCGGCUCACUGCAACCUUUGCCUCCUGGGUUCAAGCAAUUCUCUUGCCUCAUCCUCCCGAGUAGCUGGGACUACAGGAGCGUGCCACCAUACCUGGCUAAUUUUUAUAUUUUUUUAGUAGAGACAGGGUUUCAUCAUGUUGCUCAUGCUGGUCUCGAACUCCUGAUCUCAAGAGAUCCGCCCACCUCAGGCUCCCAAAGUGUGGGAUUAUAGGUGUGAGCCACCGCGUCUGGCUGAAAAGCACUUUCAAUGAGACUGUGUUGAAUAAAGGGCCAAGGUUCUUGCCACCCAGCACUCAUGGGGGCUCUCUCCCCUAGAUGGCUGCUCCUCCCACAACACAGCCACAGCAGUGGCAGCCCUGGGUGGCUUCCUAUACAUCCUGGCAGAAUACCCCCCAGCAAACAGAGAGCCACACCCAUCCACACCGCCACCACCAAGCAGCCGCUGAGACGGACGGUUCCAUGCCAGCUGCCUGGAGGAGGAACAGACCCCUUUAGUCCUCAUCCCUUAGAUCCUGGAGGGCACGGAUCACAUCCUGGGAAGAAGGCAUCUGGAGGAUAAGCAAAGCCACCCCGACACCCAAUCUUGGAAGCCCUGAGUAGGCAAGGCCAGGGUAGGUGGGGGCCGGGAGGGACCCAGGUGUGAACGGAUGAAUAAAGUUCAACUGCAACUGA